GUUAGAGCUGGGGGACUCUUCAGAGUCAAAGGCCAGAGAGCAUGGAGCUGAGUGGAGCCACCAUGGCCCGGGGGCUCGCUGUCCUGCUAGUCUUGUUCCUGCAUAUCAAGAACCUGCCUGCCCAGGCUGCGGACACAUGUCCAGAGGUGAAGGUGGUGGGCCUGGAGGGCUCUGACAAGCUCACCAUUCUCCGAGGCUGCCCGGGGCUGCCCGGGGCCCCAGGGCCAAAGGGAGAGGCAGGUGUCAUUGGAGAGAGAGGAGAACGCGGUCUCCCUGGAGCCCCUGGAAAGGCAGGACCAGUGGGGCCCAAAGGAGACCGAGGAGAGAAGGGGAUGCGUGGAGAGAAAGGAGACGCUGGGCAGUCUCAGUCGUGUGCGACAGGCCCACGCAACUGCAAGGACCUGCUAGACCGGGGGUAUUUCCUGAGCGGCUGGCACACCAUCUACCUGCCCGACUGCCGGCCCCUGACUGUGCUCUGUGACAUGGACACGGACGGAGGGGGCUGGACCGUUUUCCAGCGGAGGAUGGAUGGCUCUGUGGACUUCUAUCGGGACUGGGCCGCAUACAAGCAGGGCUUCGGCAGUCAGCUGGGGGAGUUCUGGCUGGGGAAUGACAACAUCCACGCCCUGACUGCCCAGGGAAGCAGCGAGCUCCGUGUAGACCUGGUGGACUUUGAGGGCAACCACCAGUUUGCUAAGUACAAAUCAUUCAAGGUGGCUGACGAGGCAGAGAAGUACAAGCUGGUACUGGGAGCCUUUGUCGGGGGCAGUGCGGGUAAUUCUCUAACGGGCCACAACAACAACUUCUUCUCCACCAAAGACCAAGACAAUGAUGUGAGUUCUUCGAAUUGUGCUGAGAAGUUCCAAGGAGCCUGGUGGUACGCCGACUGUCAUGCUUCAAACCUCAAUGGUCUCUACCUCAUGGGACCCCAUGAGAGCUAUGCCAAUGGUAUCAACUGGAGUGCGGCGAAGGGGUACAAAUAUAGCUACAAGGUGUCAGAGAUGAAGGUGCGGCCCGCCUAGACGGGCCAGGACCCCUCCACAUGCACCUGCUAGUGGGGAGGCCACACCCACAAGCGCUGCGUCGUGGAAGUCACCCCAUUUCCCCAGCCAGACACACUCCCAUGACGCCCACAGCUGCCCCUUUGCCCCCAGCUCAGUCAAGCCGCCACAUGCCCACAACCUCACCAGAGGGAGAAUUAUGUUUCUAAAUAUGUUUACUUUGGGACAGAAAAGUUUUACCAGUUUCAAUGUGUGUUUCUUGAACACCAGUGGUUUUGAUCACUUUCCUGUGUCUGUUGCACGGCAGGUCUUUCCCUGGAAUUUGGUAAGUCGGGAAGAGUCAGGACCCUUAUUUAGCAGAUGGCACUACCGAUGUUCAGGGAGGUUGAGUGACUUUUGCGAGGAUUUUCCACCUCCAGUAAUUGACACAGGGCGAUCCUCACCUCCACCCCCAAGCCUCCCCCAUCCCCCCAUGCCUCACUCACAACACUUCACACUUCUUGAAAAAGGUCACUUUGGGGUCCAGAAAACACUUACUAAAAAGGGGGAAAGUUUAGUAGGAACUUUUCUGCUUCCCACCACGGCAGAGUUCAUGCUUUGGGCUGGCUGGCUGCUGGGAAGAGAUAAACACUUAGCACUCACUAAGUGAGCGCCUGGUCAGCCACCUGCACAGAGAAGAUUCCGAAGAGGCCUUCCUCCCACACACAGACCUCAGCUAGAGGGGACCGCGGACCUCAGUGGGAAAAGCUGCACAAGGCUUCUAGGAGAUGAUGGAGAAGGGGCUUCUCCAGCUCCCAGGCCAGGGGAGAUUUCUCAACCACGACCUAAGAAGCAUCAAAGGGAAUGUGGCAAGUGUGACUCCAUUCAAAUCAAGAGCUCCCACUUACCGAAGGACACUAAGGGAACCAAAGGAAGGCCAGAGGGGCAGAAUCAACGUGCGGCACACAAAUCUUUAGUUUUCUACUAUUGCCGCAACCAGUCACCACAAAUGGAGUGGCUUGAAACAACAAGAACUCGCCACCUCCUGGCUCAGUAGAUCUGGAGUCCCUGGGCCUUACUGGGCCAGCAGGCAGGACUCAGCAGUGGUGGCUCCUUCCAGGGUUCUAGGGGAGAACCUGCUUCCUUGCCUUUUCCAGCCCCAGGGGUCACUGGCAUUCAUUGGCCCGGACUCCUUCCCCCAACCCCAAAGCCAGCAGCACCACAUCUCUCUGACCCUUCAUCCGUUGUCCCCUCUCCCCCCAAGCCCCAUGGGACAGGGUCUCCACUCCUGAGACUCAUGGGAUUAGACUAGGCCUACCUGGAUGAUCUGGGAUCCUCUCCCAUGUCCAGGUCUCUAUCCCUAACCACAUCAGCAAAGUCUCUUUUGCCAUGGAAGGUAUUUGCAGGCUCUGACUUUGUGUGUAUUAGGGCAGGACAUUUUUGGCGGGGCAGUGGUGGGGGCAGGGAAUUAUUCUGCCUACCAUGCCUUAUACAAAAAUAAAUAAAUCACAGGCUUAUACCUGAAAGAAUUCCUGCAAAUAAUAAAAGAAUUAGAGCAGCUCAGUUAAAUAAAAAAAGGUAUGAGAUGUGAACAGACACUUCACAGAAGAUGACAUGCAGGGGAGCAAGGUAUUUAUCAAAAAGUGCUCCACUUUUCACUUACCAGAGAAAUGCAAAUCAGCACCCAAAGGAGUCACUGCGGCACCCUCAUCUGAGCCUCAGAAGUUAGAAAGAUGGAUAGCACCAGUGUCAAAGGUGACUGUGGGAGGGAGAUUUGCAUACACUGCUAGUAACAAUGCGAAUUGAUGGAACCAACCUGGAAAAUGGCUUGGCAUCAACUGUUGGAGAAGAAGACACACAGUCCUCUAACCUGCCAGUCCCACAUCAGGGCCUGGAUAUGGCCGUCAUGUGUACCAGGGAGCAUGGCCAGGAAUCUUUACAGCCAAAUACUCACCAUAGCACCAAACUGGAAUCAGCCGACAUACCCAUCAGGAAGAGAAUGGAUGUUAAAAAAUGCAAGGAUAGCCAUUGGGUAGAACGCCAUACAGCCAUGACAAUUACACAGUGACACCUACACACAAGGAGCAUGAGUCUCACAAACAUGGCAGCAAAAGGAGCCUGUUCAAGAGGGUAUGUGCUAUGGAUUCCAUUGUAGAUAAAGUUUUUCAAAAGCAAAAGUAGCCAAUGGUAUUUUGGAUGCAUAUUUAGGUGGUAAAUGUAUACAGGAAAAAUAAGAAAGUGAUUGUAUUUGAGGGUGGGACCACAUGGUGACUGGGAAGGGACAGGGACAAGCCUCUGGGGUUCUGGCAAUGCUCUGUUUCUUGACCCAGGUGGUGAUUGUAAGGAUGUUUGUUAACUAGUGAUGAAAAUAAUUAAGCUGUACUUUUGCUUUAUACACUUUUGAGUACAUGUUAUGUUCCACAAUUUAAAAACUACUUAUAAAGAAACUGCACAUGCUUGGAUCCAGGAACAUGAGCUACAGGCACAUCCUCCACUGAUGCCCAGUGUUCUUGACUCAAUACCUGUAAGGAGAGGUCCUUGUAGCCCAUUGGGGGCUGACCAGACCCUACUACGCCCCUGCCACAAUCUCUAGUCCAUCACAAAAUCCACUAUUGGGAUAGUACUUUCGUCCCUCAGUAGGUAAGCAUUUUUACAACCUAGGAAGACUUAGCUUUAAGUCUAGAAAUGAUUAGUAUAAAUAUAAAAUAUAAAUAUGAUUAAUAUAAAUAUAAAAUAGCCAUAGAAAUAUGCCUUUUAGUUUGUUUUUUGAGACAGAGUUUUACUCUGCCACCCAGGCUGGAGUGCAGUGGCGUGAUCUCAGCUCACUGCAAUCUCCACCUCCCAGGUUCAAGAGAUUCUCAUGCUUCAGCCUCCCAAGUAGCUGGGAUCACAGGCACACACAACCAUGCCCAGCAAUUUUUUUGUAUUUUUAGUAGAGAUGGGGUUUCGCCGUGUUGGCCAGGCUGGUCUUGAACUCCCGACCUCAAGUGAUCCACCCGCCUCUGCCUCCCAAAUUGCUGAGAUUACAGGCGUGAGACACUGUGCCUGGCCAAAAUAUGCCUUUUGUAUUAAGGAAUCUGGACAGGUUUGAUUUUUCACAGUCUUGUAAUGUUUAAAUAAUUUGGCCUAUUAUGAAGAAUCUCACAAAUCCAAUAUAAAAUGUGGAACUAACUAAUCAAAAUCAUCUUGUAAUAUUACAUGGAAAUCUUAGUGCGUUUAUACACGGUAUUGGCAUAUUUAAGAGACUUUGAGCUCAUUGCAUUUCUAAGUUAAAUUAUUAGAUUUCUUAAGAUUUAAGUUAAAUUAUUAGAUUUUUAAAGAUUAAUUAGUGCUAAGGAGGGUUUUCUCAUUAGACAGCUGAAAUGCCGCAGGAGAAAUUUGAGUGUAUUCCACUUCUUAUUGCAAUUUUAAAUGUUUGAAGUUAUUUAAAGAACUAAAUUUAUGGUAUCCAAAAGCUCUAAAAAGGUGACUCUUAAGAUUUGCAGGUCUUAUAAAUAGAAAAACAAGAACUGUAAGCCAAACUUAAAAUAUUCAGGAUGAAUUGAGUUUUUGAAUUUGUAGCUUUCAGAAACUGAACAUUAAUUUUAAGAAGCAAAGCAGGCUGGGCACAGUGGCUCACGCCUGUAAUCCUAGCACUUUAGGAGGCUGAAGUGGGUGGAUCACUUGAGAUCAGGAGUUCAAGACCAGCCUGGCCAACAUGAUGAAACCUCCUCUCUACUAAAAAUACAAAACUCCGCCAGAAAUCGCUUGAUCCCGGGAGGUGGAGGUUGCAGUGAGCUGAGAUCGUGCCACUGCACUCCAGCCUGGGGAACAGAGCGAGAUUCCGCCUCAAAAAAAAAAUAAAAAUAAAAAGAAGAAGAAGAAGAAGGAGAAAGAGGGAGAGGGAGAGGGAGAGGGAGAGGGAGAGGGAGAGGGAGAAGAAGAAGAAGAAGAAGAAGAAGAAGAAGAAGAAGAAGAAGAAGAAGAAGAAGAAGAGGAAGAGGAAGAGGAAGAGGAAGAGGAAGAGGAAGAGGAAGAAGAAGAAGAAGAGGAAGAAGAAGAAGAAGCAGCAGCAGCGGCCAGGCGCGGUGGCUCACGCUUGUAAUCCCAGCACUUUGGGAGGCCGAGGCGGGCGGAUCACAAGGUCAGGAGAUCAAGACCAUCCUGGCUAACAUGAUGAAACCCCGUCUCUACUAAAAAUACAAAAAAAUUAGCCGUUCAUGGUGGGGGAUGCCUAUCGUCCCAGCUACUCGAGAAGCUGAGGCAGGAGAAUGGCGUGAACCCAGGAGGCAGAGGUUGAAGUGAGCCGAGAUCGCACCACUGCACUCCAGCCUGGGCGACAGAGCGAGACUCUGUCUCAAAAUAAAAGAAGCAAAGCAAGCUUAUGAAGAGAUGAAGAGUCUUUUCCCAUCACCAAUUCCUCCCCAACUCACAUCAGCAGAACUGAGAGAGCUUUUGUGAUUUGAGGGAUAAAGCUGAAUGGGUGAAAAGAAAUCAAGCCCUCCUCCUCUUGGGCCAGUGCUCUUCUUCCUGGCCAUGGGACCUCUCAAGUAGGAGUGUAGGCGUGGGCCCAUCCAGCAACAUUUGGGCAUUCGUGGACAUCCACAUAGUGUUGUUUCUGUUCUUUUCCUCUCCUUCCUCAUCUUCUCUCGUCUUUGUUGAAUAUUUUUAUUAUCCCGUCACCUCCUCUAUCAGCUUAUAACUUGUUCAUUCUUUUCCUAUCUUUUGGUGUUUAUGCUUGCGAUUGCAAUAUAUAGCCUUGAUUUUUUACGGUAUACUAUAAAUUAUUCCUUCUACCACUUUACCAAUGAAGACUUUGAAACACCUCUAACUACAUUCACUCCCUUCUGCUUUUUAUGCCAUUCUUGCCGCCAUGCUAUGAUACAUUUAUUUAAAGUCCUGCAAGAAAUGGCUAUUAGUAUUGUUUUGUGCAGUCCGUAUUCAUUUUUACCACAUUUUUACACUUUAUGUUGCCCUUUAUUCCUUCUUCUAUUUUAUUAUUAUUAUUAUUUUUGGUGUGAGAUCAUCUUCUUGCUGCCUGACAAACUCCCUUUCAUAUAUAUUUUUUAUUUUUAUUUUUUGAAACAGGGUCUCACUCUGUCCCCCAGGCUGGAGUGCAGCGGUAUGACCUUAGCUCACUGCAACCUCCACCUCCUGGGCUCAAACAAUUCUCCUGCCUCAGCUUCCCGUGUAGCUGGGACUACAGGUGUGCACCACUACGCUGGGCUAAUUUUUGUAUUUUUUGGUAGAGAUGGGGUUUCGCCAUGUUAGCCAGGCUGCUCUUGAACUCCUGACCUCAAGUGAUCCACCCGCCUCAGCCUCCCAAAGUGCUAGGAUUACAGAUGUGAGACACCGUGCCCAGCCUCAUAUAUUUUUUGAUGAAAGUCUGCUGAGGAUGAAUUCUGUCCACUUUUAUUAUCUGAAAACAUCUUUAUUUUGCCUCAUUUUAAAUAGUAUUUAGAUUGGGUGUAGACUUCUAUAUUGCCAAUUAGUUUCUUUUAGCACUGUAAAUACAGAUGUCCAGUAUUUUCAGAUUCAGUUAUUUCAGCUGAAAAGCUAGCUGAAAGUCUUGUUGCUCCUCUGAAGGUAAUAUGACUUUUUUCAAAAAAUACAUUUAUAAAAUUUUUUUUCUUUGCCUUGAUAGUUUUACUACAAGGUGCCUGGAUGAGACUUUCUCUGAAUUUGUCUUGCUUGGGGUUCAUAGAAUCUGUGACUUGAUGUCUUUCAUGAGUUUUGAAAAAUGCUAGCCAUUAUCUCUUAAAUAUUGCUAUUACUCUACUCCCUCUUCUCUUUCAGAUAUUUCAGUUACACCAAUGGCCAAUGUUUGCUCGUGUCUCAUAUGUCUCUUGUUCUAGUUUCUGGAUUUGUAUUCUUUUUUCCUUUUCACAUUCAGUCUGGAUAUUUUCUGCUGACCUAUAUUCCAGUUCACUAAUAAUGCUUUUCACUGUAUCUAAUUUGCUUAUAAAUAGAAAACCAUUGAUUGAGUUAUUAAUUUCAGUUAUAGAAUAGCCAGUGUAGACUCCAAUGCUUGGCUCCACUUCUCCACUUUUUCACCUAUUUUUUUCACCAUCUUCCAUUUUCUUCAACACACCAGUCAGAGUCGUUUUUAAAGACAUUUUAAACACCUCAGUGGCCUGUAGAUCUUAUCUUCUGUUUUUUGUUUCUUUUUAAUCUUAGUUUUUUGGCACACUUGGAGGGUUUUGAUUGAAUGCUAGACAUAGUAUUCAGGAAGGCAGAGAGGAUUUUUUUUUAAGUCAGAUUUUUUGAGGUAUAAUUUAAUACAGUAAAAUUCACCUAUUUUAGUUCAGUUCUAAGAGUUUCCUCUGUGACUUUUCCUUUGGCCCAUGGUUUAUUUAAAAUUGUGUUCUUUUACUUCCAAAUUAUUUGGGAUUUUUCUAGAUAUCUUUCUGUUCUUGAUUUCUGGCUUACCUCUAUCAGGGUCAGAGAACAAACUUAAUAUGAUUUCAAUUAUUUUAAAUUUGCCAAUGUUUAUUUUAUGGCCCAGAAUAUGGUCUAUGUUGGUGAAAGUUCAAUUUGAACUUGAAAAGAAUAUGUUUUAUGCUGUUGUCUACUGAAAAGUCUAUAUAUAAAAAAUAGAUUAAUAAACUGAUUAAUAGCCUGGUUCACCA